CCCUCCAGUCUUUCCUCUAAGAAGUUAAUCACUCUUAUUAAACAUACAUUUUCUUCCUAUCUGAAGGUAUGGGGAGCUGAUGCAGGCCAGCAGGACUUUGGAAAUAUGACAUGCCUUGUUUAUGUUACUAAUCUGUUCUGGUUGGAGAAAAAAAGUGUGUACCAAUACACUAUCUUAACUGAAGCAUGUUUAAGCUAUUGCUGGAAUUUUAAGUCUCUGGGGGACUUGAGAGGAGGGGCUUCCUGUAUAUUUUUUCAUUAAUCCUAGUUCAGCUUUUUUAGAUUGAUAUUAAAUAAAAAUGUUUAGCUUAUUAUGGGAUAAAAAAUAGAUAAUUUAGCAACUAUUCUUUAUUAUUAUUAAAAUAAAUAGUUUGCUACUUAUCUAUCUCCAUAAGAGAAAAACGAAGAACUUGGGAGAUGAUAAUUUUUAUACUGAUGGCAAAAAUUUCCCAUGGUUUUAGGACUUUGAAGCAUUUUAGUUCAGGCUGAAGUUCAUUGGUCAGUCAUUCCUAAUCGGAAGAAAUAAUGCUUGACAGUAUCACUUGAUUGUAAUAAUAAGCAAGAUAUUACUUAUGAUCUAAAAUAAUGUUACCUUUUCAUAUAGGACAUCUCCUUUUCUUUAAAGUACAUAAUAUUUAAUUACAUUAAUAUUUUAUUAAUAGCCAUUACAUGUGGUGAAUGUGAUCCUUAGAGAGGGAACAUUUCAUCAACUUUAGGACUUUAAAUAAUUUUGGACUUUUUUAGAGGGAGGAAUGUGGUUCUGAUCAGUAAAACAAUUGCACCUAUAAAGCUACAGUCUUGGAAGGAUGGUACUUGAAAAGUGGUUGUGUUAUCAAAGAAUAAUUGAAAGGCAACUGUGAGCAAUCCUCCUAAAAACAGUGGAAUUAACAGGCAGACAAAUGCCUGAAGCCUUUACAGUUCCUCUGUAGGUCUGGUAAGAGUCUUUGGUGCUGUCAACCUUUUUUGUGCAUUGCUCCUGGUGGGCUUUGUAAGUUUCAGCAUUUGUACAGAAUUCUUCUAUUCGUAGUCCUCUGUGUGACAAACCAUGGAACAGAUUUCUUGUUCUUUACAUGAAUAAUGCAAGAAAAAUUUUAUGACUUCUUAUCCCUUGCUUUUGCCCUAGUAAAAAUAUUUAUGUUUAAUUGUAGUUAUAAGGAUCCUAUAUAAAAUUUAGGUGUAAAUAACCUUUUACGUGGAUAAAGGAAUUUGUCCUAUUAAAUCAAGGAUUUUGCUUCCCCUUCAUUAGUUCUGUAGUCUCUCUCUGACUUCAGAAAGACUUAAGUCAAGAAGAUACCAGGAUGGGGACUUACAAAGAGCUGCAUUUAAGGCGUUGUCACAGGUAGAAAAAGUGACCUGCAUUUAACUGCUCUAUGUGCAUCCAGAUUCUCCUUUUACCGGUGAGCAACUACUCAAACAGAUGGUGUCUUUUGAAAAGGUGAAACUCACCAACAAUGAACUGGAUCAACAUGGCCAUAUAAUUUUGAACUCAAUGCAUAAGUACCAGCCAAGGGUGCACAUCAUUAAGAAGAAAGACCACACAGCCUCAUUGCUCAACCUGAAGUCUGAAGAAUUUAGAACUUUCAUCUUUCCAGAAACAGUUUUUACGGCAGUCACUGCCUACCAGAAUCAACUGAUAACGAAGCUGAAAAUAGAUAGCAAUCCUUUUGCCAAAGGAUUCCGGGAUUCCUCCAGGCUCACUGACAUUGAGAGGGAAAGUGUGGAGAGCCUGAUUCAAAAGCAUUCCUAUGCACGCUCACCCAUCCGUACCUACGGAGGAGAAGAAGAUGUCUUGGGGGAUGAGAGUCAGACAACCCCAAAUCGAGGGUCAGCCUUUACAACAUCUGAUAAUUUGUCUCUCAGCUCCUGGGUAUCAUCUUCUUCCAGUUUUCCUGGGUUUCAGCACCCACAGUCCCUGACUGCUCUUGGCACCAGCACAGCAUCCAUAGCAACACCCAUUCCUCACCCCAUCCAGGGUUCUCUGCCACCAUAUAGCCGACUGGGAAUGCCUCUGACACCAUCGGCCAUUGCCAGCUCCAUGCAAGGGAGUGGCCCCACAUUCCCUUCAUUCCACAUGCCGCGAUACCAUCACUAUUUUCAGCAGGGGCCCUAUGCUGCCAUUCAAGGACUACGCCAUUCCUCUGCUGUGAUGACGCCAUUUGUAUGA